CCCCCAGGGAUAAGGUUCUUGCCAUCCUUGGUAUUGGUAUGGCUGCUUUUCUGGAUUUGAGGUGUCCACGCCUCUGCAUGUGUCCCCACCGUAAGGCUGAGGACCCCUCUCGGAUGCAGGUGCCCCCGGCUCAUGCUUCCAAAACCCCCUCUUGAUUUGUCACUGUAUGGGGUAAGGCAUAGUUUCCUGGCUGUGUGGAUGUAAGAUACCUGAGUCUCAAGCGGGAGACUCCACUGUAGACCCUGUCCCUGGGACCAGAGACUUCUCUGGUGUAGACUUUCCAAGGUGGGAGAUUCCAGCCCCCCACCCUUGGCAUGGGGCAUCUCAGUGGAGAUGACUACCUCUACCCCAGGCCCUAACGCAUCCUUCUUCUGGAGUCUCAGAGCCUCUGUGUGGCCACGUCAGCAGCCACCUGGGUUAAGGAUCACCCUUCAACAUCACUUCUCAGAGCUCCUUGCUGCAGAGGCGGAAGCUCUCCCAGAUCAAAGGUGCCUCAUGACAAAGACCACUCUGUGGGCACAUGACGGCCCCCAAGGUUAAGGACCACCCGGUGUUAGUUUCCCAGGGCUGACCUCCUGCCCCUCCCUCCUCGAGUCUUUGUGUGGUGGUAUCAUCUUCCCUGAGAUGAAGUCUGGGGGGCUCUUCUUUACUGGUUUUGGCUCUGAUUUUAGCGUGUUGGCUCCUGUGAGGCUGGUGUCCUGCUCACCUCCCCCCGCCCCGCCACCCGCCUUGUGGGUCCCUUCCCUGUGGGGAUGUGUGUUCCUCUUGGGUAAGUCUCCUCCUGGGCCGAGGUUCCCAGAUUCCUCAGUGCUCUUGGAGAGCCUUUGCUGCUGGAGCACAGGUUCUUCACGCCUGAGAGUGGACCUGCGAUCACCACCUUCCUUGGAGGAUCUUGGUGGAUGCCCCCCUGACUACAGCAAAUGGGGCUCUUUCUUCUCUGGCGGCGUCUCUGCUUCGAGACUCAGGCUCCAGCUUCCCUUCUCUCUGGUCCUUUGCUGGGGGGACCAGAGGUACAGAUACCCUCAUGAUAUAAGGAUUUUCUUAGCGGGGAAGGUGUUGUCUCUACUGUGGCUAAGGCUCCAGCCUCUCUAGGGGACAAGUACCCUGGGCCUCUGGCACUUGCCCCUUCUCUGUGGAGGAGCUGCCUCCUCACUGGGUCUCAGCUGUAGCCGACUUCGAUGUCACACUGUUCUGUCUGAAACAUCACCUCCCUGGGUUAGCGCUCUUGUUCCCCUCCUUCUGGCUUGUGACCCCUCCAGGACUUCCUUCUCUUGCUGCCACAGUGUGGUCUCCUCUCUGUGGGUAUUCUUCCUCUGCACUAGGAUACCAGUCCUUUCCGUGUGGAGACACAGGGAGGGCGUCACCUGCCUAAGGUGUUGAUUGCCUUGUUUAGGGGUGUAGACCAUGAGACCUCUUCUCUCUCUGGGCUGGAGCACCUGCCCAUGACCCUCUGUUGGGUUCUUGGGAUGGAAAGAGGGAGUGUAAACUCUCGUUUCACAUUCUUGUUCCCCCUAUGCAGUAAGAGGCUUUUCUGUGUUGGGGUGUUGGACUUUGGUGAGGAUCCCUGCACACCUGAGCUCUGGUGUCCAGGCCCUUGCCUUGUGUGAGCUCCCUGGGUCAAAGGGGCUUUCCCCUCCUCAGCCUGAAUCCCCACUGUGGCACCUUCUCCUGGGUCCUUUUGUUGGUUGCUUUGCCUUCUUAGAGAUUCCCCAGGUAGGGCGUGAUAGCUGACCUGGGCGGGGGCUGCUGCGGCUUUCUUUAGGUUGGGCCUUUUACUGAGGAGAUUUAAAUUCCCUCAAGUGUAAGGUAGCACCCCUACCUAUUAUCACCCAGAAUGGGUCCCUGCGGUGUUGGGAAAAUUCUCCCUGGGGGUAAGGUACCAGCCCUGUCCUUUAUGGGCUUCUUGUUCUAAAGCAUAUCCGUCCCAUAUGGUUGCUGCUAGUCACAUGUGGUGAUUAGUAACUAGUUAAAAAUGAAAAAUUCAGUUCCUCCAUUACACUUGCCACAUUUCAGAUGUUCAGUGGCCAACAGAUAUGCGCAAAUAGAGUGUUUCCAGCAUUGCAAAGUUCUGUUGGAUAGCACUGUUUGCCAGAUGUUCCCUUCUUUGUGGGUGAGGACUCUUUUGGUGUGACUUCCCUCUGUAUUGAGGCUCUUGUUCCUCAGUAUGGGGCUGUUUCUGUCUUUACAGUAAGUGACUACUCCAGGGUUCCCUGCCCUGCACACGUAGAGUGGGAGCGGCCCGUGGAUCCCAGGGAACUGUGCUUUUCAUUGUAGGCCCCCUCCCUGGAGGGGAAGAGGGCAAUCUCCGCUGGUAUCUCAGAAGUCUUCUUCUGAGGCAUAAGCCUCUCUUCCCAGGGCUCCCCUGGUCUCGCUGUCAGGCCCUAAGGUAUGUCUUCCCUUGGACUAAAGCUCCUUGGAACUCCCUUUUGACCUCAGUCUUCUCUGGGUUCCAGGUAACUUCCUUUAAAAUAAAGACGCUCCUCUCUUGAAGUUUUGGGUUCCUGCCCUGAUGGUCUAUGUCUCCCUGACUCUAAAUUACCAAUCCACUUGCUAUGGGAUUCCUCCAUGAGUGCAGAUCGGCUCCCUCACAGCUGCGGUACCUUUGCACCCUCUUAUCUUAGUAAGAUUUCUGUCUUCUCCCAGGUCUCUCUUGGGUACUGCCUUCUGCCCCCAAAUCUCUAAGCCUUCUUGGUAUUAGCUUCUUUGGGUUAGGAGUGUUAUUUCCUUUUGGUUUAAGGAUCCUGCUCUGGAAUAAAUGUCUUGGUGGUUUGAGUCCCUUCUACUUGGCAUUCAGCCCUGUCUGCAUGAGCGGGUUCAGCUCUUCACAGCUUUCGGCAUCUCUGCUCGCCGUCGUUUUCCCCCACCCCCAAUCUUUCUUCUCCUACCUACAGCUUACACACACACACACACACACACACACACACACACACACGCCCUUCUCUGUGAGCUGCCAGUUUCAUUUGUCUCCUGACUUGUCUGAGGGAUGACCUCUCCUAGCCACCUCUGCCCAGCCCCUCUGAGUAGGAAGUGUGAUUUCCAGGGCUAAUGCCUCCAUCCCAGUCAUCAGCUGUGUGCAGCAUGACUGUCCUGCUCUGAAAAACCUUUUUGAGUGUAUUCUGGGGAGAAGGUACUCCAUGCUCUAGGAAUUUUCCACUUCCUGAGUCAGAGGCACACAAAAAACGUCCGUCUCCAAGAGAGUAUGAAGAGAGUGCGUCUGUAGGGCAGGGAAGAUGGCGGACAAGCGCAAACUCCAAGGUGAGAUUGAUCGCUGCCUCAAGAAGGUGUCCGAGGGCGUGGAGCAGUUUGAAGAUAUUUGGCAGAAGCUCCACAAUGCAGCCAACGCGAACCAGAAAGAAAAGUAUGAGGCUGACCUAAAGAAGGAGAUUAAGAAGCUACAACGGCUGAGGGACCAAAUCAAGACAUGGGUAGCGUCCAACGAGAUCAAGGACAAGAGGCAGCUUAUAGACAACCGCAAGCUCAUUGAGACGCAAAUGGAACGGUUCAAAGUUGUGGAACGAGAGACCAAAACCAAAGCUUACAGCAAAGAGGGCCUGGGCCUGGCCCAGAAGGUAGAUCCUGCCCAGAAGGAGAAGGAAGAGGUUGGCCAGUGGCUCACGAAUACCAUCGACACGCUCAACAUGCAGGUGGACCAGUUUGAGAGUGAAGUGGAGUCACUGUCAGUGCAGACACGCAAGAAGAAGGGCGACAAGGAUAAGCAGGACCGGAUUGAGGGCUUGAAGCGGCACAUCGAGAAGCACCGCUACCACGUGCGCAUGCUAGAGACCAUCCUGCGCAUGCUGGACAAUGACUCCAUCCUCGUUGACGCCAUCCGCAAGAUCAAGGACGACGUUGAGUACUAUGUUGACUCAUCCCAGGACCCCGACUUCGAGGAGAACGAGUUUCUCUACGAUGACCUGGACCUCGAGGACAUUCCACAGGCGCUGGUCGCCACCUCCCCUCCCAGCCACAGCCACAUGGAGGAUGAGAUCUUCAACCAGUCCAGCAGCACGCCCACCUCAACCACCUCCAGCUCUCCCAUCCCGCCCAGCCCAGCCAACUGUACCACGGAAAACUCUGAAGAUGAUAAGAAGAGGGGACGUUCCACAGACAGUGAAGUCAGCCAGUCUCCAGCCAAAAACGGCUCCAAGCCUGUCCACAGCAACCAGCACCCUCAGUCCCCAGCUGUGCCGCCCACCUACCCCUCCGGCCCCCCGCCUGCUGCCUCUGCCUUGAGCACCACUCCUGGCAACAAUGGGGUCCCCGCCCCCGCAGCACCCCCAAGUGCCCUGGGCCCCAAGGCCAGUCCAGCUCCCAGCCACAACUCGGGCACCCCUGCUCCCUAUGCCCAGGCUGUGGCCCCACCAGCUCCCAGUGGGCCCAGCACGACCCAGCCCCGGCCCCCCAGCGUCCAGCCUAGCGGAGGCGGAGGCGGCGGCAGCGGAGGUGGAGGGAGCAGCAGCAGUAGUAACAGCAGUGCCGGUGGAGGGGCUGGCAAGCAGAAUGGCGCCACCAGUUACAGCUCAGUUGUGGCAGACAGCCCGGCAGAGGUGGCUUUGAGCAGCAGUGGGGGCAACAAUGCCAGCAGCCAGGCCUUGGGCCCCCCUUCCGGCCCCCACAACCCACCUCCCAGCACCUCGAAGGAACCCAGUGCGGCAGCCCCAACGGGGGCUGGGGGCGUGGCCCCAGGCUCAGGGAACAACUCAGGGGGACCCAGCCUCCUGGUGCCACUGCCUGUGAAUCCUCCCAGCUCCCCAACGCCCAGCUUCAGUGAUGCCAAGGCAGCCGGUGCCCUGCUCAAUGGGCCUCCACAGUUCAGCACCGCCCCAGAAAUCAAGGCCCCUGAGCCUCUGAGCUCCUUGAAGUCCAUGGCGGAACGGGCAGCCAUCAGCUCUGGCAUUGAGGACCCUGUGCCAACGCUGCACCUGACCGAGCGAGACAUCAUCCUGAGCAGUACAUCAGCACCUCCGGCCUCAGCCCAGCCGCCCCUGCAGCUGUCAGAGGUGAACAUACCGCUGUCGCUGGGUGUCUGUCCACUGGGCCCUGUGCCCCUCACCAAGGAGCAGCUCUAUCAGCAGGCCAUGGAAGAGGCCGCCUGGCACCACAUGCCUCACCCCUCUGACUCUGAGCGUAUUCGGCAGUACCUCCCCCGGAACCCCUGUCCGACGCCCCCCUACCACCACCAGAUGCCACCCCCACACUCGGACACUGUGGAAUUCUACCAGCGCCUGUCGACCGAGACACUCUUCUUCAUCUUCUACUAUCUGGAGGGCACUAAGGCACAGUAUCUGGCAGCCAAGGCCCUAAAGAAGCAGUCAUGGCGAUUCCACACCAAGUACAUGAUGUGGUUCCAGAGGCACGAGGAGCCCAAGACCAUCACUGACGAGUUUGAGCAGGUGAGGGCCCCGCCCCCUCUCUUCCCGCUGCUAGGGUUGGGGUAGAGUCCCCAGGCUCCAGGCAGCCCCUGCUGGCCUCUGCUCCCUUGCCUCCACCUUUCAGCUGGCGCAGUCCCUCAGCCUGACCAAGUACUCCUCCCUCUGGCUGUCUGCUCAGCCUGGAACACCGCCCUCUCAUCCUCCACUUGGCCAGCUCCUAGGCCUCCUGUAGGUCUCAGCCCAAAUGUCCCUUCCUCAAAGAAACCUUCCUGGAGCCACCCAGCCCAGUGCCUCCCCUUUGCAGUGCUGGGCACACUCGCUUGGGGUGUGGGAUUUUCCCAGUAUGUGUCCCUGCACCAGGCUGUGGGCUCUGCUGCCGAGGGACCUUGAUGGCCCCCACUUCACCUCCAGGUCCCAGCACUCAGCAGGGCAGGGGCUCAGUGCCGAAACUAUUUUUUUUGAAUGGGCUUCUCAAGUUCUAAUACUGGGAAAUUCCUGCUGCUUGCAAACACUCUGGAACCAACCUACCUGGGUUUCAGCCCAGUCCAGCUGGGCGACUCUAGGCAAGUCACUCGAACCUCUGUGUCUCAAUUAACUUAUCUGUAAAAAUGGGGGGAAGACCACCUACCUAAUGCAGUUGUUAUGAAGAUUAAAUGAGUUAAUAACAUGUAAGUACUUAAUGGUGACUGCUACAUAGUCAGUGUCAUGGAUUUUUUUUUUCAAAUUACUUUCAGUUGGUGUGUUCUACAGUGAUGUUUUUUUCCACCAAAUACUUCCCUGAUGCCGAGCCCCUUCAUGGGGAUGAAGUAGUACAAGGUCCUUGUCCUCAGAGAACUCAGUCCCCUCUCCUGGUUCUCCCAGGUUGCCAUCUUUGAAGCACUUAAGACAUUCAUUUAGAACCUAGGUCCUCUCCCAUUGUGUCCUCAGAUGUUAACCACAGACUUCCUGUCCUUUCCUGGUUUGGCCCAAAACCAUCCUCCAAGUUAGUACAUUUCAGGGCAUCCAGUCAUUCAGAAAUUCCCACACCACUUCCGUCACCAAUAAAAUGUCCCUGCAGAGUGCUUGGAUUUAGACUCUGAGACUGUUCCAUUCUCUAGAACAAGGGUGACAGUACCCACUGCCUCGAGGUCUUUGUGAAGAUUAAAUGCUAGGCUGUGCAUCCUGUACUCACGUGAGAGGUGCUCAAAAGCCACAGCCCUCGAGGAAACGAAGGCUGUGCACUCACACCUGGGGCUGGGGCCCCGUUCUGGCAGCUGGCUUCGGUGGAACCUCUGCGGCCCCCUCCGUUUCCUCCUCGCUGAAGUGGCAUGAUAACAUUUCCUACCCAAGAAGAACCUUGUGAGGAUGGAUGAGAGUGUGUGCGUGCAGGGCAGCUGGCCCGGUGCCUGACACAUCCACAGCCCUAAGAAUUGUCCCCUUUGUCUGUUGGUCCGGCCCAGAUCCCAGACCACCUCCUCGUCCACUCACUGACCGCCUUCUCCCCCGGCCAGGGCACCUACAUCUACUUUGACUACGAGAAGUGGGGCCAGCGGAAGAAGGAAGGCUUCACCUUUGAGUACCGCUACCUGGAGGACCGGGACCUCCAGUGACACCGGCCCCUCCCUCUACCCACCCCCUUCCCCCGCAUGCUGAUCCCCCUGCCCAGGUGAGGGCCCUGCCCUGGAAGACUGGAGGGAGGCCCCAAGCCACGGGGCAUCCCCCUCUCCCAGGAAGCAGGGAGGGGGCCGGGAGGUUUUCCUCUCAGCCCCACCCUGGGGGCCCGGGGGCGAGGGCUGCCCCCUCCUCCCCUCCCCAGUGAGGGACAUUUUUUGGUAAACCUAUUUUCAUUUUGGAAAAUAUUUAUGAAUAAAUAGUUUUAUAUGA